AGUCAAAGCGGCUGCGGGCUUGGGGACCCGGCCCGGGCAGCGGAGCUUCCGGACCCGCCGACCCGCCGAGGAGCGCGCGUCGGGCUCCCGUCGAGCAGCUGAGCCCGUGUGCCCCGCGUCCCGCGCCCCGAAGCUGCCGCUCCGAACUUUGGUCGGCGCUGCCCAGGCUCCCCGCCAGGGACCAGCCGGGAAUUUUCAAAAUGAAUUAUACAGAGUCCAGCCCAUUGAGAGAAUCAACUGCCAUAGGUUUUACACCUGAGUUAGAAAGUAUCAUACCUGUGCCUUCCAAUAAGACCACUUGUGAAAACUGGAGAGAGAUACAUCAUCUGGUUUUUCAUGUAGCAAAUAUUUGUUUUGCAGUUGGGUUGGUUAUUCCAACUACUCUUCACCUUCAUAUGAUAUUUCUUAGGGGAAUGUUAACUCUAGGAUGUACCCUUUAUAUCGUCUGGGCCACUCUCUACCGAUGUGCCUUGGAUAUAAUGAUCUGGAACUCUGUGUUCUUGGGUGUCAACAUUUUGCAUCUGUCGUAUCUUUUAUACAAGAAGAGACCGGUAAAGAUUGAAAAGGAACUCAGUGGCAUGUACCGGCGAUUGUUUGAACCACUCCGUGUGCCUCCAGAUUUGUUCAGAAGACUAACUGGACAGUUUUGCAUGAUCCAAACCUUGAAAAAGGGCCAAACUUAUGCUGCAGAGGAUAAAACCUCAGUUGAUGACCGUCUGAGUAUUCUCUUGAAGGGAAAAAUGAAGGUCUCCUAUCGAGGACAUUUUCUGCAUAACAUUUACCCCUGUGCCUUUAUAGAUUCUCCUGAAUUUAGAUCAACUCAGAUGCACAAAGGUGAAAAAUUCCAGGUCACCAUUAUUGCAGAUGAUAACUGCAGAUUUUUAUGCUGGUCAAGAGAAAGAUUAACAUACUUUCUGGAAUCAGAACCUUUCUUGUAUGAAAUCUUUAGGUAUCUUAUUGGAAAAGACAUCACAAAUAAGCUCUACUCAUUGAAUGAUCCCACCUUAAAUGAUAAAAAAGCCAAAAAGCUGGAACAUCAGCUCAGCCUCUGCACACAGAUCUCCAUGUUGGAAAUGAGGAACAGUAUAGCCAGCUCCAGUGACAGUGACGACGGCUUGCACCAGUUUCUUCGGGGUACCUCCAGCAUGUCCUCUCUUCAUGUGUCAUCCCCACACCAGCGAGCCUCUGCCAAGAUGAAACCGAUAGAAGAAGGAGCAGAAGAUGAUGAUGACGUUUUUGAACCGGCAUCUCCAAAUACAUUGAAAGUCCAUCAGCUGCCUUGAUCAGAGAGAGAAUUCAGGUUACCAAGACGGAAGGUGUCUUGAAGAGAUCCUGAAAAAUACCAGCACUUUUUCAUGGCUUUUAGGUUAUUCUGCUUUAGUGCAUCCAGACUGGUGGAGUCGGAGGGAGGAAGUGAGGAAGGGUCAAGGAUGGAAGAGUUCUUUCACUUACCCUUUUUAUUAGUCAGCUUUUAAAGUAAUUGUUUUACUGAGCCUUCUGACUAUGCCUUGUUCUCUUUUGAGAUAUAUAUUUUCACAGUCUUUUCUAGAUAUAUUAUUGUUUUAACUUAACAAAUCUUAGCAAUCUCUCAAUGCCUUUUCACUUAUUUUUUUCCAAGUUAUGAUUCUUUUUCCUCACAGUCUUUUUUGUUCCAUAGCAAUGAGGUUGUCCAUUUGAUAAUUUUAACAAACAAUGUAAGUUUAAAAUUGAGGCUAAGGUAACAUGAAAAAGCAGGGAAUCUCAAACUUUAUUCCAUAUAUACACACACACACACACACACACACACACACAUACAUACAUACAUAUAUAUAUAUAUAUACAUAUAUAUACAUACACACAUACAUAUAAUUUUUUUUUUUUUUGAGAUGGAGUUUCACUCUGUCGCCCAGGCUGGAGUGUAGUGGCACAUUCUCAGCUCACUGCAAACUCCACCUCCUGGAUUCACGCCACUCUCCUGCCUCAGCCUCCCGAGUAGCUGGGACUACAGGCACCUGCCACCGCGCCCAGCUAAUUUUUUUGUAUUUUUAGUAGAGAUGGGGUUUCACUGUGUUAGCCAGGAUGGUCUCGAUCUCCUGACCUCGUGAUCCGCCCACCUUGGCCUCCCAGAGUGCUGGGAUUACAGGCGUGAGCCACCGCGCCCGGCCUAUUCCAUAUUUUUUUAAUGGGACAUUUUAGAGAAAGGUGUGAUUUGACUGGUUUUAUUUUUCUCCCAGGCCAGAAGUAUUACUCCACUAGAUCACCUUACUUAAUUGGGCACUGUGUGGAUAACUUGAUAAUGAACAAAACUCUCAGAUUUUACUCACAUUACCCUUGUAUUAUGCCAUUUAUAAACUGCUCUGAAACCUGAAGCUGGAAAGAUAACAGAUGGGUUUCUGAGCACGGGGUUAACCUCCAGCUAAACUCAACUUCCUUGGGAUUUGGAGUCACCAUGUUGUGCACACUCUGGUGUGGGAAACACUUUAUGUAGGGUGGGAGGACAGGGGAGUUAAAUGGCUGGGCAGGUGCCACAGGAUGAGGCCACUGAAAGAUCUGCUUCAUUCUUUGAUCUGUAUUCUGAAGUUCCAGAUUGUUCAUCUAGAGGCAGAGACAUCUCUUUUAAAAAAGUGCCAGAUGCCCCAGUGCCAGAGCUGCGAACGUGAACACAGUGGAAGGCAGAGGGUUUACUACAGGCCAGGCCAUGGACACCCCACCCAGGUACUGCAGUGAGGGCCUUGAUUCCAGAGCUCUUUUUCCUACUGAAAUCAUGGUUUAGUAAACAGUGGCAUUUGGCUGGUGGGAAAUGCGUAACUGGUCAGUGUGUCUGGCCAGCGUGGCUGUGGCACUUGGCCAGGACGCUCCGUUGAAUGAAGCUCAUUGAUUGGCCAUGCUGGUCAUGUCUAUUUUGCUUCAUCCACUAGAACCAACUUUGAGUCAGUCUCCUGUUACGUUAAAUGGCUAAGAAAAGUUCCAAAUGAAGUUGUUCUCAGGUGAACUGAGCCAAAAGAAGCAACUCUUACCAUGAGGUGAUUUCUGUUAGAGGAGACAUAUAAAUAAGCUCAUCUAGGGUCACCUCAUUUUCCUAAAUAUGUUUUUAAAGCAAUUAUUGUAGUAAUUUCAUUUGAGUUAAAUUUACAUGCUCGGUCACUCAUUGAGAAAAUUUACACAGACUCUGAAUCCAGUUCCUGUCAUCUUCAGAUGUUGGUUUAUUGACAUCACAGUAAAAAGGCUACUGUCGACUGGACACAGUGGCUCACACAUGUAAUCACAGCACUUUGGGGGGCCAAGGUGGGUGGAUUGCUUAAGCCCAGGAGUUCAAGACCAGCCUGGGCAACAUGGCUAAACCCCAUCUCUACAAAAAAAAUUAGCUGGGUGUGGUGGUACAUACCUGUAGUCCCAGCUACUCAGAAGGCUGAGGUGGGAGGUUCACUUGAACCUGGGAGGUUGAGGUUGCAGUGAGCACAGAUCACACCACUGCACUCCAGCCUGGGCAACAGAGUGAGACCCUAUUUCAAAAAAAGGCUGCUUUCACUGUACUGCUGCAGCAGUCUCUUCAGGUAGCUAAAUUAGGAGCUUGUUUUGGAGAAAUGAAGCAAAGGUGAAUGACAGCCUAGGCUUGAAAUUAUAAAGCUCUCUCAGGUUGAACUCUCUCGUGCGCUCUCGCUCUCACUUUCGCCCUGUACCUGAGAGCACAGGUGUAACUGUGAUGUCAUAGUGCCGAGACUACUUUCCUUUAACCAUUGGGGUUAAGUUGGGCAGCCCAUUUAGUUUACACGCGCAUAAGACUAAUUUACAAAAUCACUCUAUACAGUCAUUAGAUGUAACAUCCUUCCCUGAGUAGAAAGUAAUGCAUGUGUUUGGAGAUUAUUUUCUGUAAUGCUGGGAACAAACCUGUUUUAAAAGCACACUGCUAAAAGUAGGUGAUAUAAGACCAUUUGCUGUUUUUAUUAAAGUAUGUGUGUGUAUCAGUGUCUCAAUGUGAAGAUUGUAACCUCAAGAUUAGGAAUCUUAAAAGAGCCACUUAGCCUGAAUGGGAAACGUGAGACUAUUUUUAAACACACACCUCUAAGGAAGAAGCCUCCCAUAUAGACUUGAUCUCAAAGAAGCAGAUAAGAAGACAGAAAAGUGUUUUAAGUGUAAGAUCUCCUAUGGAGUACUUUAAAUUCAUUUAUACAAAUGAAUAAGUGUAUCUUUGUAUAAUGCAUAAAUACAUAGAUAAAAACAUGUUUGCUGCCAAAGUUCCCAAUAAGAUGCUUCCUGUGUUUUUUGGCCUUUACUUAGCUGAAUGAUCAAAGUUCAGAAAAUGGUCUGCAAAAGUUACUCCAUAUACAACCCCAAAUCUACUACUUUAAAUGUAACAUCAACUCAGUUGUAUGAAUCUGGAGUGUAAUAUUUAUAUUAGAAUGUAUAUGUCAUUUAAAAUAUUUUGAAAGCCCUCAUAAAUAUUUAUAUUUACUAAACUAAUAGCAUAGACACUAUAUAAAUCCGCAGUGAUGCUUAUAUAUCUUAAAUUAGUAAUAAUGGGUGCUAUAUAAUUAUUUUCAGUUACUAUCCCUGACACUCUGGAAUCUUCUCCAUUUCUCCCUAUCACUCAAUUUCAUUUUAAUCAUUGGACACCUUUGCGUUUUGCUGCUAACAGUGUGUGUAUGUCACCCUCUUUAUAUCUGGUUUUCCCACUUGUCUGAAGCUCUCCUGAUCUUAGAACCUGGAGCUGCAGAUUCCUCCAUGUCAGCUCCCAUCACGGCCCCAAAGACAGAGUCACUUGGUUGCUGAGUCACUUGGUUGCUGGAAAAAUCUUUGGGGAAAGCUGGUAUAAGCUACACACUGACCUGUCCCCAGUGUUUCCAGGUAAUGACUUGGCACUCCAGAGAAAGUUUCAUGCUGUUGCGUGUGGUGGCUCCAAGCCAAGCACCUGGCAUGCAGGUCAGCCCUUCCCAGCGGGCGUGGCGUCGUCCUCUUCACAGAUGCCACGUUGCAGCCCCAAGGCCUCACCAUUUUGCGUUUUUUAGAAACCCAUUUUCUUGGUCAUUUAUAAAGCUGCUUUAUAGAUAUCUUUGAUCCUGGCAUGCCUUGGUUUCCUCUCCCUUCCCUCUUUCCAAUCCUGGUUUCCUAACCUCCUCUUGUAGUAAUUCUCAACUCAACUCAAAGUCCCAAGAAUUUGGAAUGGUAGGAUGCUGUGCGGGGAGCUCGAGGCUGAGGCAUAAUCACUGCUUCGGUUCUGCUCAUCAGGGGACACGCUCCCUUACUCAUGGCAGCCAUGUUUGAUUGUCACAGAGCCCCCCGAAUACUCUGUCUAUAGUGACACACUGUAGGUGUCAUAAAUUUUAAGAAACCUGCUUUUAAGUACUAUUUAUAGGUUUUUCUGUUAUACUUGCAACCUAGUUUUAAAAUACAUGAGGAUUUUAUGAAAGCUUUAUACAGACAUUUAUAGGAAACUCAUUCUUUGAUUUUAGGUGCCAUUUAAAUUGAUAACACUUACUUUAUAAAAAGAUGCUUUUUGUCUGGAUAGAGCCUUAUAGUUUAAAAUAUCUUCAUAUAUUGCCAUUUGAUCAAAUAAAUUUCUUACUUAGAAAA